GUCAUUUCUCGGCGCCGGGAAACCUGCCAUUCUUCGCUGCUGAUCGCGGGAUUCUUUUUGGAUAGGGUUGACGUUCGUGGAUAGACUCAUAUCUGUGACCAGUGUCCGCCACCGCGGAUGGCAAGAGACCUGAUCGGACCGGCCCUGCCGCCCGGCUUCAAGGCCCGCGGAACAGCGGAGGACGAAGAGCGGGACCCGAGCCCUGUUGCAGGACCAGCUCUGCCCCCUAAUUAUAAAAGCAGUAGUUCAGAUUCAUCAGACAGCGAUGAAGACAGUAGUUCUUUGUACGAAGAAGGAAAUCAAGAAUCUGAAGAAGAUGACAGUGGUCCAACUGCAAGAAAACAGAGGAAAAAUCAGGAUGAUGACGAUGAUGAUGAUGAUGGGUUUUUUGGACCAGCCCUUCCUCCUGGAUUUAAAAAGCAGGAUGAUUCUCCUCCAAGGCCCAUAAUAGGUCCUGCAUUGCCACCUGGUUUCAUUAAAUCUACACAGAAAAGUGACAAGGGCAGAGAUGAUCCAGGACAACAGGAAACAGACAGCAGUGAAGAUGAGGAUAUUAUUGGACCAAUGCCUGCAAAAGGACCAGUUAACUAUAAUGUAACGACAGAGUUUGAAAAAAGGGCCCAGAGAAUGAAAGAAAAACUGACCAAAGGAGAUGAUGAUUCAUCUAAACCCAUUGUAAGAGAGUCAUGGAUGACUGAACUUCCUCCAGAAAUGAAAGACUUUGGUCUUGGGCCAAGGACUUUUAAGAGAAGAGCUGAUGACACAUCUGGAGAUCGAUCAAUCUGGACAGAUACUCCAGCUGAUAGGGAAAGGAAAGCUAAGGAAACACAAGAAGCAAGGAAGUCAUCCAGUAAGAAAGAUGAAGAACAUAUAUUAUCAGGAAGAGAUAAGAGACUGGCUGAGCAGGUAUCUUCAUACAAUGAAUCAAAAAGAUCAGAAUCUCUUAUGGACAUACAUCAUAAAAAGUUAAAGAGUAAGGCUGCUGAAGACAAAAAUAAGCCUCAAGAGAGAAUACCAUUUGACCGUGAUAAAGAUCUCAAGGUUAAUCGGUUUGAUGAAGCUCAGAAAAAAGCCCUAAUAAAAAAAUCUAGAGAACUAAACACCAGAUUUUCACACGGCAAAGGCAAUAUGUUUUUAUAAGGGGAUUUCCCUGUGCAAUGAAGAAAAGUUGAAGAAUACUCUUUGUCCAUCUUUAUUUCUUUGUUUUUGGCUUCUUAAGAUUAGAGAUUACUUUAAUCUUAAAAAACAUACAAAUUUACCUUGUUCUGUAUGUCCUUUUAAGGUCAUGUGGAAACAUAAAACGAAUGUUUUUUAUGUAGAACAGAAUAUUCUAUGUGCCUUUAGCUUCUGUGGAAGUAUGGGGAAUUAUGGGCUUUUCUUCAAAUAAUUAUUUUAAGAGGCUUCCAUUCCCCCUGAUUUUUGUGGUGUCUCACAAGUACCCUCUAAGGUCUGGUCAGGACUGACCACCAAAUCUCUACCACAGCCUGGACCUCCUUGUGAAAUAUACCUAACCUGCCCUAGAGUCAGUGUGUCAAGUCCUUACUGUAAAUCCAUGACUUUGAAAUUUGUUGUUUUUUCCCUUUAAACUGCAGCCAGUGAAUACAAAUUUACUUGAAAAUAGAGGGUAUGGGGUUUUGCCUGUUUUGUAAUCAGUUUGCUUGUUUUAGCACUCAGGGCUUUUUAUUUGUUAUUUAAUUUUUUAAUUGUUUUUAAGUCAGAAAGAUCUCUGGGUUAUCUCAUGUGCUAAGGAAAAACUAUUUUGCUUUUUCCAACUUUAAUAGUUAGUAUUUCUAGGGGAGGCAAUCAAGAUAAGAUAUGCCAUUAACUGUUAGCAUUGUGAAAUCUGUAAGACUCAAUCUCUGAUCUCAACCAAAGCUUUCUGAGUCCUGGAACUUUGCUUUGGGACAACUUUACUUUACCCAUUUAUAUGCUGUACUUAACAGUUUGUAGCUAAUUUAUGGGGUCAUAUCUUUUUUUUAGCUAAUUUACGGGGGUCAUAUCAGUCAUGAAUAGCCUUUUUUAAAAAUUUAAUAAUCCCUGAAUACAAAAAUGGAAAUGGAAAAUUUAUAAUCAUAACCCCCCUAAUUGGGAGUAUUAUAAGUUUGUAAUGCUUUAAGCACUGCCUCUUAAGAUGAUAAAUUUAUAAGAUGAGAAAUUCUAUUUAAACUAUUAAACUAUUGUUAAAUAAAUGCCAAUUCUAUAAGUUAUAUUUUCUUGCAGAUUAAUCCCAAUUGUUCCACUAGUAUUCUAGUUUUGAUGAGACACAAAUUUUUGUUGUUGUUUAUUUUUGUUUUUUUGAGAGAUGGAGUCUUGCUCUGUCACCCAGGCUGGAGUAGAGUGGCGUGAUCUCAGCUUACUGCAACCUCCGCCUCCUGGGUUCAAGCGAUUCUCCUGCCUCAGUGUCCCAAGUAGCUGGGACUACAGGCGUGCACCACCAUGCUCAGCUAAUUUUUGUAUUUUUUAGUAGAGAUGGGGUUUCACUAUAUAUUGUUCCAGGCUGGUCUCGAACUCCAGACCUCAGGUGAUCUACCUGCCUCGGCCUCCCAAAAUGCUGGGAUUACAGGCAUCAGCCACCAUGCCUGGCCAAGACACAAAUUUUUAAUGGAAAAAUAUUCUGAUUCCCAGUUCAUGUAAGCUUUAUGAAAAUUGAGUAUAUUGUUUAUAUGAUGGUACAAAUUAUUCUUCCUCUAAUAAUAGCAGUACAGUAUAUUUUUUCCAUAGCAUCAGUGUAAACCAUAGCAAACUAAAGGAGCAUUGCUAUUAAAAAGAUGAAUUAGCUGGGCGCAGUGGCUCAUACCUAUAAUCCCAGCACUUUGGGAGGCCGAGGUGGGUGGAUCACCUGAGGUCAGGAGUUCAAGACCAGCCUGACCAACAUGGUGAAAUCCUGUCUCUAUUAAAAAUAUAAAAAUUAGUCGGGCCUGGUGGCGGGUGCCUGUAAUCCCAGCUACUCAGGAGGCUGAAGCAGGAUAAUUGCUUGAACCUAGGAGGCGGAGGUUGCAGUGAGCCAAGAUCACACCAUUGCAUUCCAGCCUGGGCAACAAGAGUGAAACUCCAUCUCUAAAUAAAUAAGUAAAUAAAUAGAUGAAUUUUUCUCCUAAGCAAAUUGAAAAAGCUUCUUGUGUACUCAAAAUUGAACAGAGCUACCUUUUGACUAAAAAUGUCAUUUUUAAUGAGCAGUAUUUUCUGAACACAAAAUUUUGUACAAGAGUGUCUCCAUUGCAUUAAUUUAAUUUUGUUAUAAUUUUUUCCCAAUGAAAGGAAAAAAGUAUUUUGUAGCUCCUCUUCCUUAUGUAAAUUCUUAACAUAUAUUUUUGAGAAAUUUGCAUUUUUUAAAGUAAAAUUGUUAUCUUUGGAUACUUACUUUUCUUUGUUUUCCUCAUUUAAAGAGAAUAGGGAUAUUUCUGUAUUAUAUAUUUACUGUUUCAUCCCUCACCUUUGGAGUGACCAUGACCUUGGCAUGAAGGAGAGAAACCUCUGCUUUCCGCCUAUUGCUUCCAGGAGUUACUACCUUACUGGCCUUGGAGAUAAUGCUCUUUUGUGCCAACCUGAGGAUAAUUUUAACAAAAUGUAAGGCCAGUUUCAGAGGUUGUUUUGCCCCACAGAGAGACUAAUCCCAAUACAAGAAUAUUGACAACAAAAGGACAAAGUAGUUAUUGCACAGGACGGAAAGGUGUCUUUAUUUCAUCCCCUCCCCACUUCCAAAGAUGCAAAAGGCCUAAUUGAAUCAAGUCUCCUUUCCAUCUGGCAGGAGACAUUUUAAUAAGGACUUUUUAAUUUCCUACAUUUCUUGGCCAAGUGUCAUAGGAAUGUGGCCUCUUUUGAAAUUUAAAAAUGAAGAAGAAAAAAAGAGCAACACUAAGUUAAUAUAAUGGAGCAGAUACUUUUAAUGUUCUUACCAUUGAAUAUGCCAUUUAAGUUUGUUAUACUUGAAAUUAUAUGAUUUUUGUCCAGCUCUCUAAAUUGUCAUCUCCAAUAGAUUUAGAUGCUUCAAAUAGUAACCACAUUACUGUGAUAGGUAUUAUUAGAAAAAAGUUAUUUCUUGAGUUACACCUAAGAGGAAGAAGUAACAUGAUGGAAAGUGGUUGGAGAUAGCACCCAAUUAACAUCGACAGCCAAGUCUUCUAUUUCAGAAUAUUGAUUUAUUUCGCUUUGGCUUUUGAUGCCAUCAUGAGAUUUAAGUCUGCAGUUUCAAAAGCUCAUGCUACUUAGAUGAUUUUUGCAGCUUAAAAAAUUGCUUGUGACUGCAGUAUGUACACAGUUAAAAAGCUGUUCACUGCCCCUUUCAACCUUUUCAUUUUGAGCUUUACUAAGAGAAUGCUUUUAGGAACAGAAUUCCUAAAGUGUAAUUUUUUAUGUAUAAAUAAAGUUUUAUCUAUAUCUGAGAAGUUGUAGUAUUUAUUUUUGUUUUAACAUUAUUAGCUUUUCUGAAGCAGGCAGUAUUGGUAAAGAGAAUAUUCUGUAAAGGUUUAUUCCGGCCAACCAGAUCAUUGUAGGCUAUUGUAAAAAACAACAACAACUUUAACUCCAACUCGCUUGCCAGGUUUUCAUUAUCUAAUAUAACUAUACAGAUAUUAUCUGUUUAUUUAGAAACACAAGACAGACAAACUGGAAAUGUUCUUGAGAGCACUGUGACACUGGGUUAUAACCAAGAUUCCAUUGUUCUUCAUAUCACAGGACCUGUAACAGUGGGUAGGUUUUUUCUGGAUUGUUUGAGUAUGAGUUUCUUUGGUUUGGUUUGGUUUGGUCUCUCUAACUCCCAAAUUGAAAGUGACCAAAAGAGAUGCUUUGCAACAUCAAAGCUAAGCAUUGAAUGAUAGGAAUCUGAACAUGUAGGGUCAAAAAGAGAGCCUUUGCUUUCUCAGAUCAUUUCCCUAUAAUAAGUAUUUCUGGAGGAACUUAUAUGUUUGUUCAUUUAUUCAAUAAACAUUUAUUAAAUGCCUCAGUGUAUGCUAGGUGCUAAGAACACAAUGGUGAACCAGGCAGGCAUAGUCUUCCUCCCUGGGAGAAGAUUCUGUGCUGGUCCCUUAUAGGGUAUUCACAGAUAAGUAAAGCAGAUUCCUUGAUUUGUGAUUUUAUAUUCUAGUGGGAGAGCAGAAAAAGAUCUGAGUAAAAAAGAUCAAGUAAUUGCACAUUGUUGAUAGGUGUUAGAAAGAAAACACGGUAGUGAAAGACUAGAACAAGUAGUUGAGGAUGGGAAUUCUAUCUAGUUAGAGUGAUAAGAAGUCUCUGAAGAUGUGUCAUUUAAGCUGAAACCUAAAAAAAUGAAAAGCUAGCAGUGUGAAAAGUGACUGAUCACAUAUGCAAAUGCCCUGAAGCUUUAGUUCUUUGGUGUUUGAGGAACUGCUCCAGUAUGGCGGGUAUAUUGUGAGAAAUAUGAUGGUUCAGGGUUGGGUCUUCAUAGUGUCUACUGAUACUAUGAAGCCUAUAUAGGAACAUCUAACCCAGUCCUGGGAGGUGAAAGGAAGCUUCCUAAUGGAGAAUACUUUUUUAUUUUUAUUUCUUUUUUUUUUUUUUUAUUUUUUUUUUUUGAGACAGAGUCUCCCUCUGUCGCCCAGACUGGAGUGUAAUGGCGCAAUCUCGGCUCACUGCACCCUCCGCCUUCCAGGUUCAAGUGAUUCUCCUGCCUCAGCCUCCUGAUAGCUGGGAUUACAGGCACCCGCCACCACACCCGGCUGAUUUCUGUAUUUUUAGUAGAGACAGGGUUUCGCCAUGUUGGCCAGGCUGGUCUUUUUUUUUUUUUUUUUUUUUGAGACGGAGUCUGGCUCUGUCUCUCAGGCUGGAGUGCAGUGGCGCCAUCUCGGCUCACUGCAAGCUCCGCCUCUCGGGUUCACGCCAUUCUCCUGCCUCAGCCUCCCCAGUAGCUGGGACUACAGGCGCCCACCACCACGCCCGGCUAAUUUUUUGUAUUAUUAGUAGAGACGGGGUUUCACCGUGUUAGCCAGGAUGGUCUCGAUCUCCUGACCUGUUGAUCCAUCCGCCUUGGCCUCCCAAAGUGCUGGGAUUACAGGCGUGAGCCACCGCCCCCGGCCUCCAAUGGAGAAUACUUCUUAACCAAGUUAUAAACAUGACAUUGGAGUUGGCCAGAUGGUUCUUACACCAAAGGUCUACUCUGCUGGCCUUCCAGAAUUGCCCAAAUGUGUCUGAAUUCACUCUUAGGCCCUUGCUCUGCAAACACCCUGUAUGUAACUCCACUAAUAACUGUCAUUAGUUAUCAGAACAUUAAUACAUUGAUCUGAACAUUGAGCCUAUACUUUAUCAUCAAAACCAUAAAUAUUUAAGAAUAGCUGUUUUUUUAAGAAGUUGUUGUAAAUUACUUGUUUCCUCCUGGGCCUAAUUAUUGAGGGUUAUUUACAUUCUUUUUAAGAACUGAAUAGCACCAGAUGAAUUCAACAAUUAUUAGUCAAGUCUCUAGAAUUCUGGACAUAGCAGAAUGUUUUUACUUAGGGACUGAAAAAUACAGUAGAUCAGUCUGUCUCUUAAUUUGUAAUCCUUAAACUAUUUCUAUCAGAAUCACCUAGGAGUUCAUUUAAAUGCAGAUCUCCAGGCCCAAACCUAUUGAAUAGGAAUCUUUGGGGUUAGAAUCAGAGCAUCUUCACUUUUAACAAUUAUCCCAGGCCAUUCUUUGUAAAUUCAAGUUUAAGAACCACUGCAUUUAUGGGCAGACAAGGUAGCUCACACCUGUAAUCUCAGCACUUUGGAGGGCCAAGGUGGGAGGAUUGCUUGAGGCCAGGAGUUCAAGGCUACCCUGGCCAACAUGGUGAAACCCUGACUCUAAAAAGAAAUUUAAAAAAAUAAUAACCACCGCACUUACAUGUGUUCCUAUAAACAAUCCCCUCUCCUUUGUUAUAUGUUCUGUUUUCCUAUUAUAUAUUCCUAAAUACAUAAUCACUUUACUUUGCAUAGCAACAAACACCAGCACCAGCAAUACUUGCCUCUUGAAGAAUGGAUUGUCACUUCUCUUGAGUGAAUGCCUAAAAGCAUUCACCCUUCAAACAUCUACCAGCCAGUUGCUACAGUGAUCAAGAUUCUACUGCCAUUGAUAAUUCAGUUUCAUUGCACUUUGCCCUCUCUUCAGCACCUUUUAAAAUAGAUAAGUCCCUAAGAGGAAUAGUCAGAUUGUAGUUCCUUGUCCCUGGCUGACUUGGGGCCAUUUAAGACUGAAUGCCUCAGGAAUGCAGAACAUUGAAAAGGCAGGGAGCACAAAAAGGGAGCACUGGUGGGCUAUAGAUGAUCUGCAAAGGAUGGUCUCUACCUUAUGACUAUUUUCCUUGGGGGAAUUAACCAGUUAAUGUUACUUUGAGGUCUUAGAUAACUGUGCUUUGGCAGCUAAGGUAUUAACUUCAGAAGCAACUGAGUUUACUUUUAGAUACCAGUUUCUGUAUUUGCUGACAAAGAAAAGAUAACAGUAGGUAAAAGAAUGUUAAAAAGAAACAAAAGGCCAGGCACAAUGCCUCACAUCUGUAAUCCCAGCACUUCAAGAGGCCAAGACAGGAGGAUCACUUGAGGGCCAGGAGUUCAAGACCAACCUGGGCAACGUGGCAUGACCCUGUCUCUACAAAAAAAUAAAAAUUAAAAAUUAUCUGGGCAUGGUGGCAUGGCAUGCAUCUGUAGUCCCAGCUACUCAGGAAGCUAAGGCAGGAGGAUCACUUGAGCCCAAGAGUUCAAGGCUGCAGUGAGCUAUGAACAUGCCACUGCACUCCAGCCAGGGAGACAGAGAGACCCCAUCUCUAAAAGAGAAAAAAAGAAAGCAAUAAAAUUCUGCAGAACUAGGUAGGAAAGACAAUAAAAGCUACAAGGGUGCAUCAUUGUUUUGAGAUCUAGACAAAUUUCGAGAACCUAUUCAAGAAUAUUGAAAAGUAUUUCAAAGUUCAUUUUCAUAUCUCUGAUUACUUACCGCUGUCCUGCCCUUUAAAGCACUUCCAUUUGUUUUCUUUAUGAUGGGGUAAUGUUGGCCAAACAGGCUAUAUGAUAAAGUAUUUAGUCCUAGUUUUAUCUUCAUACAAUCAGAGCUCUGAGAUGAAAAUAAACUUGUUCCUUUUUUAUCACUAGGUACAAAACAACAAAUGAAGUUGCUUAUGUAUAUAAUAUGAUGAUUUUUGUCUUUUUAGGUAAUGGCUGAAAGCAACACAUUUUGCUAACCUAAGGAUAAAUAAUACUAUAAUACCUAAUUCACACUACACACUUAACAAAAGCAAUUUAUCAUCAGCCUAAGAUUGCUAAUUUUUAUAACAGGUACAGACAUAAUUAACUUAAUAUUGACCAGCAAAUAAAUCUAGAAAUUGUGCUUAUUCUUUAGUAUUCAUUUUAACUGAAUUUAAAUUAGUGUUUUUCCCUAACAGCCUUGUAUAUUGCUUAAUAAAAUUGUCAUAUUUGAAAACAGAGAUUCUUAAAGUUUAAAAUGCUUGCAGUCAAAUGACAGUUUAUCAAUAAAGAUUUAAAACUA